GUCCCCGGGUAGAGGUGCGUUUGCAGGAGUAUGUGUGUGUGUGUGUGUGUGUGUGUGUUUGUGGAGAGAGGCCCUUCCCUCCCCAGUUCCUGCAGCCUCGGCUCCCAAGGAGGGAGACCCCUGCGAGAAGCCGUGGGGGAGGGAAGGGCGCUCUGCGGCGGAAUGAAGUGGUCCUCGGCGUUCCUGCGUAGAGCCCAAUAUGGGUGUCCCUUGUUUAGGGCCGUUACCGAGUGUCCGGGUCGGUUCUUGAGGGUAUUUGGAGACGGGAUGCAUGGGUCACAUAGACAAGCCUCGAGAAUGGGAGCCGUUACAUUUUUGCACUGCCUGGUAACAAGGGAUCUUCUGCAGAAAUAGCGCUGGAAGCUAGAGUGAGGCCUGAGUACUGCCUUGGCCUAGGAUGGCUAGAGAAUUAAGUGAAAGCACAGCCCUGGAUGCCCAGUCUACAGAAGACCAGAUGGAGCUUCUGGUCAUAAAGGUGGAGGAAGAAGAAGCCGGUUUUCCCAGUAGCCCAGAUCUGGGUUCUGAGGGCUCCCGCGAGCGCUUCCGAGGCUUCCGCUACCCGGAGGCUGCAGGCCCCCGCGAGGCGCUGAGUCGGCUCCGAGAGCUCUGCCGACAGUGGCUGCAGCCUGAGAUGCACAGCAAGGAGCAGAUCCUGGAGCUGCUGGUGCUGGAGCAGUUCCUGACCAUCCUGCCGGGGAAUCUGCAGAGCUGGGUGCGGGAGCAGCAUCCAGAGAGCGGGGAGGAGGUGGUGGUGCUAUUGGAGUAUUUGGAGAGGCAGCUGGAUGAGCCGGCGCCGCAGGUAGAAAGAACAGGUUUAGUAUCUGAGCGCUGUGGCCUGUUUCCUCCUGAAAUCCCAGAUCAGAGUGAGGGGCAUUCCUUUAACAUCCAGGAGUUCUUCAUCUCUUUUUUGUACCGUGAACCUCCUUGGCAGUAAGGUGAAGUCCCUGGACUCCUUCUCAGAAUAAUUUUUUUUUUAAAAUACAUAAACCAUAAAGGAUUACAAAAGAACGCAGUCAUAUCAACAUACAGUUUGCAAAGUAUUAACUUUGUAUUAAAGUCAUACUUUUUUUUAUUAGUACACUAAAUAAUAAAACCUACGGACAGGGCUUAUAACUGGCAAUUACAAAGCAGUGAUAAGUAUCUCUUUGCUUGGUUGUAAUGUGAUGUAAAAACAUCUGCAGGUUCUAUUGGUGACAAAGUCGUGGGUACUGCUUAUGCUACAUUGAUUUGUUGCUUCCAUUCAUAAUUGGAAGGAAAUGCUAACUUUCUCUUAAAGACUAGUUAAAAAUAAGAUUAGCUUUUGUCCUGUUCAAGUUCAUGGACUACGUGGGAAGGAGUUCAUGGACCACUGGUUAUGAACCUCUGGUAGAAAAUGGGCCGACUUUUACCUCCAUGUUCUUCCCUGUUUUAUGAGACUGUGUCCUCUUUGCAUCAUCCUGUGUCCCUGUGCACACACCCUCAGAGGACCUGUGUGGCCAGAGCCUUCUAAAUGGUUUCAGGUGUUGACCAGGGGCAAGAACUGCUCUGUUGCAAGAUGGCACUAUUGACACCAGCCCCAGGGUCACAAAGUAGCCAAUUUCAGCUAAUGAAGGCUCUGCUCAAGCAUGAAUCUGUGGGAUCCCAGCCUUUACAAGAUAGAGUUCUCCAGGUCCCCGUGCUUGCCCAUGGAGGAUGCUGCAGAGAAGAUAAAGUGGUAGCUUCUAGGCUUACUCCAGAGUCCCAGGGGUUGUUGAAAGUGGAAGAUGUGGCCCUGACCCUCACCCCUGAAUGGACACAGCAGGAUUCAUCUCAGGGGAAUCUCUGUAGAGAUGAAAAGCAGGAGAACCAUGGCAGCCUGGUCUCCCUGGGUGAUGAAAAACAGACUAAGAGCAGGGACUUGCCUCCAGCUGAGGAGCUUCCAGAAAAGGAGCAUGGGAAGAUAUCGUGCCACCUGAGAGAAGACAUUGCCCAGAUUCCUACAUGUGCAGAAGCUGGUGAACAGGAGGGCAGGCUACAAAGAAAGCAGAAAAAUGCCACAGGAGGGAGGCGGCACAUCUGCCAUGAAUGUGGAAAGAGUUUUGCUCAAAGCUCAGGCCUGAGUAAACACAGGAGAAUCCACACUGGUGAGAAACCCUACGAAUGUGAAGAGUGUGGCAAAGCCUUCAUUGGGAGCUCUGCCCUUGUCAUUCAUCAGAGAGUCCACACUGGUGAGAAGCCAUAUGAGUGUGAAGAAUGUGGUAAGGCCUUCAGUCAUAGCUCAGACCUUAUCAAGCAUCAGAGAACCCACACUGGGGAGAAGCCCUAUGAGUGUGAUGACUGUGGGAAGACCUUCAGCCAGAGCUGCAGCCUCCUUGAACAUCACAGAAUCCACACUGGGGAGAAGCCGUAUCAGUGCAGUAUGUGUGGCAAAGCCUUUAGGCGAAGUUCACAUCUCCUGAGACAUCAGAGGAUCCAUACUGGGGAUAAAAAUGUUCAGGAACCUGAGCAGGGAGAGGCCUGGAAAAGUAGGAUGGAAAGCCAGUUGGAAAAUGUUGAAACUCCCAUGUCUUAUAAAUGUAAUGAGUGUGAAAGAAGUUUCACUCAGAAUACAGGCCUCAUUGAACAUCAAAAAAUCCACACUGGUGAGAAACCCUAUCAGUGUAAUGCGUGUGGAAAAGGCUUCACCCGAAUUUCAUACCUUGUUCAACAUCAGAGAAGCCAUGUAGGGAAAAACAUCCUAUCACAGUGACCCAUGCCAUACAUGCCAGAGUUGGUGCUCAUUUGUCACUGAUCUGAAGCCACUCCCCCUGGAGUCUCAACUAUAGAAAUUGUGGGCUGGGCUUUAUUUACCACUACACAUUAUCAGGUGUUAGAAAAUGUAGACUGGGUUAGACAAAUUAUCUUCUAAGUUCUAGAAGGGGUUUGUAAUCAAAACAUAUUUGAUAGGAGGCUACGGGAGAGUUGUCUAGAAGAGGUAAGACCUGAAACUGUUUGUUCUCUCCCACUAGAAUUAAAUGGAUGUUUAGACUGGCUACUUGCCCUAAACCAGCACUUGGUGAUGUCUACUGGGUGGAUGGUUGUGAUUUGGGGGCUGCUUCUCUGACCAUUCUUUUUGACUGUAAUGAAUCCUCCACAGUUGGUCAGAUUCAUAAAGUCUUAUAUCCCCCUCUGUGCCUUUUCUGCAGGUGCUAAUAAAUGUUUAUUGAAUGUACCAGUGAGAUUACCUUCAUAGAUCUGAAAAUCUGAUGUUAUCCAGGUUUCUGAAGAACUUCUCGCCAAGGCCAUUUGUGCUUGUGUCCAAUUCUCUGACCUAGAUUGUGACUCAAUCUAGUGUGUUUCUUACCAAGUACAUAGGCAGAGCAGGGUUACUGUGAUUGAAAGAAUCCAUUUUUUUUUUGGAGACGUAGUCUUGCUCUGUCGCCCAGGCUGGAGUGCAGUGGCACAAUCUUGGCUCACUGCAACCUCCACCUCCUGGGUUCAAGCGAUUCUCCUGCCUCAGCCUCCUGAGUAGCUGGGAUUACAGGUGUGUGCCACCAUGCCCGGCUAAUUUUUUAUGUUUUUAGUAGAGACGGGAUUUUACCGUGUUAGCCAGGAUGGUCUCGAUCUCCUAACCUCAUGAUCCUCCUGCCUCAGCCUACCAAAGUGCUGGGAUUACAGGCAUGAGCCACCAUGCCCGGCCAAGAAUCCAUAUUUCUUUACCAGACUAGGAAUUCUAUUCUAGUGCAAAUGCCUUAAAAAGCUUAUCACUAAAUCAUUACGAAUGUGUGCCAUCCGUGGAAUUGCUUUUUUUUUUUUUUUUUUGUAAAUAUGAGGUCUCACUAUGUUGCCCAGGCUGGUCUCGAAAUCCUGGGCAAUCCUCCUGCCUCACCCUCUCAAGUACUGGAAUUACAGGCGUGAGCCACCAUACCCAGCCCAAAUUUCACUCUUUAAUGUUUUCCUGUUGCUAUUCUUUAAGGAAAAAACUUUCCUAUUCAGACAGUGUGAAAAUCAGUCAUCAAGUCAGAAUAAAAUGAUGAAUAUUCUAAUGCUCAGUAUCUUAGUUCUCUCGGGCCUAACCAAUGCCUCCUAAAACAAUAGAUACUAUCCUGCCCCACCCUACCACCCAACACACACUGUAUAGUAAACUGCAUCAAAACUUAUUCCUGCUAAGUUCAUACUUUCUCCAGCUCAAUGGAUUCACACCAAAUUUUUUUUUUUUUUUUUAGACGGAGUCUUCUCUGUCACCCAGGCUGGAGUGCAGUGGCGCGAUCUCGGCUCACUGCAAGCUCCGCCUCCCAGGUUCCUGCCAUUCUCCUGCCUCAGCCUCCCGAGUAGCUGGGACUAUAGGCGUCCGCCUCCACGCCGGGCUAUUUUUUUUUUUUAUUUUAUACUUUAAGUUCUAGGGUACAUGUGCACAACGUGCAGGUUUGUUACAUAUGUAUACAUGUGCCAUGUUGGUGUGCUGCACCCAUUAACUCGUCAUUUACAUUGGGUGUAUCUCCUAAUGCUUUCCCUCCCCCCACCCCACAACAGGCCCCAGUGUGUGAUGUUCCCCUUCCUGUGUCCAAGUGUUCUCCUUAUUCAAUUCCCACCUAUGAGUGAGAAUAUGCCGUGUUUGAUUUUUUGUUCUUGGCGAUAGUUUGCUGAGAAUGAUGAGACGAGGUUUCACUGUGUUAGCCAGGAUGCUCUCGAUCUCCUGACCUCGUGAUCCACCUGUCUCGGCCUCCCAAAAUGCUGGGAUUACAGGCGUGAGCCACCGCGCCCGGCCCAAGUAUCACUUAUGGUUUCAGAACGCCAUUAUUAGUGUCUGACUGUCUUGGUCUUCUUAUACAUUGAUUCCCAAAUCACGUGUGGUAACAGCAUCUCAAUUUUUCAUGAUGACGGUUUGAACCAUUAAUUUAAUUCCUCAGGCUAUCUACUUUUUUGUUAAACAUACUGUGUAGACCAUCUUUUUUUUUUCCCAUCAUGAUAGUCAAAAUUUUAGUCUGUGUAUUCAAGUGAGAAAAUUUUUAGUCAGCAUUAUACAAGUAGUAUUUAUUAUGUAUACAUUCAGUGGAGUUGUUUCUACAAAAGUAUUUCGGAAUGACUAUUCUGCUGCAAACUUUUGUGUAAGCGCUUCACCUUAUUCCUACAAUAAGGAGAAGUGCACUAACAAAAUGAACAAUGCAGCAAGGGCUUCAGUCGCAGCUCAGGUCUUAUCAAACACCAGAGAACCCUCAAUGGGAGAAGCCUUAUGAGUGUGACAACUGUGGAAAGACAGUUCCUUUUUUGUUAGUAUCACUUCUACUUAUUGUAGAAAUAUGCUUUCAUUAUUGCAUCUACUCACAUUUCUCACUCGGUUUCUGGCACCAGCAAUCUCUUCCAUAUUUAUAAUAUCAGUCAAAAACUCUGGAAUUCAAAUAUAACAAGACUUUUCUGGUCACCUUUGAUAGUUAAUGACUUGGGCAUUGUGAUAUAUUAUCUCCUGCUGUAUGUAUUUUGUUUAGUAGAAAUUGAAUCAUUAUCCACAAUCCUUUAUAGAACUAUCCAAGUCCCUGUUUUUAUGCUAGUUUCCAAGGCUUGGUCCUUCAAGGUUUUCAGGGAUCUAGGGGACACAAAUCUAACAAAUCCUAAUGUAUAUUAUUUGUAUUAUAGUAAUAAACCAUAUGGUUACUUUG